AGCUCGGGCUCCAGCUCCAGCGCCGGCGCUUCAGCUGCGACCGCGAGCCCUCUCAAGCAAGGUAGAGACCCCGCGAGCCCCCCAGCGCCCCACCCUCCCCCAUCGGAAAAGGACAGGGGUAGGGAAGCCGAGGACCCACGGGCUGCGUUCGUGCUGCUGGGUCGGGAAGGAGGAAGCGUGACAGCUGGAGCGGGAGAAAUGAGCCUUCCUGAGGAAGAAUGGCAAAUAUUACUGGGCAUCUCUUCAGCCUCAGCACAGACAAGCCCACAUCCCCCAACCAUGCCAGUAUCGUAACUUCCUCCUAUACUACGCAAUGACACCCUCUACACACACACACACACGCACACACACACACACACACACACACACACACAACCCCCUCAGCCAGGUGUAGCACUGCAGUCUUCAGUGUUUGUGGAGGCUUAAUAAGUUUUGAGGCUUCAAGCAAAUGAUUCCCUCUUGAGGGCUACCUACUAGCAGCAACGGUCAGGGAGAGGAGGAGGAUACAGUCUAUGAUGUGAUUAAGGAAUUCAGAAGUCCAGAUAUAACUUCCCCAAGUCACACAGUGGUAUCAGAGCUAAGAAUGGGACCCAGAUAUGACUGAUCUAGUUCUGUUCCAAAACCGUGCUGUAUUAUAUUAACGCCUACCCUCUGAAGAGGUCCAAGCAACGGAAGUACUACUACGAAGCUGCCUUUCUGGCCAUCCUUGAGAAAAAUAGACAGAUGGCCAAGGAGAGGGGCCUAAUAAGCCCCAGUGAUUUUGCCCAGCUGCAAAAAUACAUGGAAUACUCCACCAAAAAGGUCAGUGAUGUCCUAAAGCUCUUCGAGGAUGGCGAGAUGGCUAAAUAUGUCCAAGGAGAUGCCAUUGGGUACGAGGGAUUCCAGCAAUUCCUGAAAAUCUAUCUCGAAGUGGAUAAUGUUCCCAGACACCUAAGCCUGGCACUGUUUCAAUCCUUUGAGACUGGUCACUGCUUAAAUGAGACAAAUGUGACAAAAGAUGUGGUGUGUCUCAAUGAUGUUUCCUGCUACUUUUCCCUUCUGGAGGGUGGUCGGCCAGAAGACAAGUUAGAAUUCACCUUCAAGCUGUACGACACGGACAGAAAUGGGAUCCUGGACAGCUCAGAAGUGGACAAAAUUAUCCUACAGAUGAUGCGAGUGGCUGAAUACCUGGAUUGGGAUGUGUCUGAGCUGAGGCCGAUUCUUCAGGAGAUGAUGAAAGAGAUUGACUAUGAUGGCAGUGGCUCUGUCUCUCAAGCUGAGUGGGUCCGGGCUGGGGCCACCACCGUGCCACUGCUAGUGCUGCUGGGUCUGGAGAUGACUCUGAAGGACGACGGACAGCACAUGUGGAGGCCCAAGAGGUUCCCCAGACCAGUCUACUGCAAUCUGUGCGAGUCAAGCAUUGGUCUUGGCAAACAGGGACUGAGCUGUAACCUCUGUAAGUACACUGUUCACGACCAGUGUGCCAUGAAAGCCCUGCCUUGUGAAGUCAGCACCUAUGCCAAGUCUCGGAAGGACAUUGGUGUCCAAUCACAUGUGUGGGUGCGAGGAGGCUGUGAGUCCGGGCGCUGCGACCGCUGUCAGAAAAAGAUCCGGAUCUACCACAGUCUGACCGGGCUGCAUUGUGUAUGGUGCCACCUAGAGAUCCACGAUGACUGCCUGCAAGCGGUGGGCCAUGAGUGUGACUGUGGGCUGCUCCGGGAUCACAUCCUGCCUCCAUCUUCCAUCUAUCCCAGUGUCCUGGCCUCUGGACCGGAUCGUAAAAAUAGCAAAACAAGCCAGAAGACCAUGGAUGAUUUAAAUUUGAGCACCUCUGAGGCUCUGCGGAUUGACCCUGUUCCUAACACCCACCCACUUCUCGUCUUUGUCAAUCCUAAGAGUGGCGGGAAGCAGGGGCAAAGGGUGCUCUGGAAGUUCCAGUAUAUAUUAAACCCUCGACAGGUGUUCAACCUCCUAAAGGAUGGUCCUGAGAUAGGGCUCCGAUUAUUCAAGGAUGUUCCUGAUAGCCGGAUUUUGGUGUGUGGUGGAGACGGCACAGUAGGCUGGAUUCUAGAGACCAUUGACAAAGCUAACUUGCCAGUUUUGCCUCCUGUUGCUGUGUUGCCCCUGGGUACUGGAAAUGAUCUGGCUCGAUGCCUAAGAUGGGGAGGAGGUUAUGAAGGACAGAAUCUGGCAAAGAUCCUCAAGGAUUUAGAGAUGAGUAAAGUGGUACAUAUGGAUCGAUGGUCUGUGGAGGUGAUACCUCAACAAACUGAAGAAAAAAGUGACCCAGUCCCCUUUCAAAUCAUCAAUAACUACUUCUCUAUUGGCGUGGAUGCCUCUAUUGCUCAUCGAUUCCACAUCAUGCGAGAGAAAUAUCCGGAGAAGUUCAACAGCAGAAUGAAGAACAAGCUAUGGUACUUCGAAUUUGCCACAUCUGAAUCCAUCUUCUCAACAUGCAAAAAGCUGGAGGAGUCUUUGACAGUUGAGAUCUGUGGGAAACCGCUGGAUCUGAGCAACCUGUCCCUAGAAGGCAUCGCAGUGCUAAACAUCCCUAGCAUGCAUGGUGGCUCCAACCUCUGGGGUGAUACCAGGAGACCCCAUGGGGAUAUCUAUGGGAUCAACCAGGCCUUAGGUGCUACAGCUAAAGUCAUCACCGACCCUGAUAUCCUGAAAACCUGUGUACCAGACCUAAGUGACAAGAGACUGGAAGUGGUUGGGCUGGAGGGUGCAAUUGAGAUGGGCCAAAUCUAUACCAAGCUCAAGAAUGCUGGACGUCGGCUGGCCAAGUGCUCUGAGAUCACCUUCCACACCACAAAAACCCUUCCCAUGCAAAUUGACGGAGAACCCUGGAUGCAGACGCCCUGUACAAUCAAGAUCACCCACAAGAACCAGAUGCCCAUGCUCAUGGGCCCACCCCCCCGCUCCACCAAUUUCUUUGGCUUCUUGAGCUAAGGGGGACACCCUUGGCCUCCAAGCCAGCCUUGAACCCACCUCCCUGUCCCUGGACUCUACUCCCGAGGCUCUGUACAUUGCUGCCACAUACUCCUGCCAGCUUGGGGGAGUGUUCCUUCACCCUCACAGUAUUUAUUAUCCUGCACCACCUCACUGUUCCCCAUGCGCACACACAUACACACACCCCAAAACACAUACAUUGAAAGUGCCUCAUCUGAAUAAAAUGACUUGUGUUUCCCCUUUGGGAUCUGCUAA